CUGUAUUUCUCUAACCCAAAGUCCUCUGGCUAAGUCUCUAAGGUGAUGUCUGUGAGCACACAAAGCCUGCACAAUUCUAUCUAUUGGCAAAAACACUCCUCUCCUGAGCUGAUAUACCUUUGCUUAGAUAAAGGAUCCUUGAGAUCUAAACUCCACAAAACCCACAUUAGAAAAUCAAGUGUAAUCCAAUCAGGAGGUGAAGAGAGGCUUACGAAAGCAAUGUAUUAGAGAGGAAAGACCAGAGCAAGAUUUUGAAGAGAUAGCUUCUCUGGGACAUGAAGCCUGGAUGAAGAAGCACUGUGCAUAGACUCCAGGGGAAAAUGAAGGAAGUGACAAAGGGAGCAUUCACUCUUCUGCAUUGGAGAUUGGAUUUCCCGACAUGAAAUUAUAAACUAAGUAAGAAUGCUGAGUACAGAAGGAUCCAAAGUCGUGGAAGACAUCGCCAUGUGAGGAAACUGGGUGAAGAGUUCAAGGGAAUCUACGUAUGACUUUUGCCACUUCUUGUGAUUCUAGUAAUUUUAAAAUAAAAAGUCAAGGGAGAAGAAGAUUCUGUGACUACAUCUGAUCAACAUAGAUACCUUCACAGCCAUUUCUUCCUCCAGGGCAGUGGAGGUGAAACACAUAUCAAUGGUCAGCACUGAGUUCUCUGAGUGGAAGGAAGAUUUUUGAAGACAAAAAAUGCUGGCUAGAAACAACUCCUUAGUGACUGAAUUUAUUCUUGCUGGAUUAACAGAUCAUCCAGAGUUCCAGCAACCCCUCUUUUUCCUGUUUCUAGUGGUCUACAUUGUCACCAUGGUAGGCAACCUUGGCUUGAUCAUUCUUUUCGGUCUAAAUUCUCACCUCCACACACCAAUGUACUAUUUCCUCUUCAAUCUCUCCUUCAUUGAUCUCUGUUACUCCUCUGUUUUCACUCCCAAAAUGCUAAUGAACUUUGUAUCAAAAAAGAAUAUUAUCUCCUAUGUUGGGUGCAUGACUCAGCUGUUUUUCUUUCUCUUUUUUGUCAUCUCUGAAUGUUACAUGUUGACCUCAAUGGCAUAUGAUCGCUAUGUGGCCAUCUGUAAUCCAUUGCUGUAUAAGGUCACCAUGUCCCAUCAGGUCUGUUCUAUGCUCACUUUUGCUGCUUACAUAAUGGGAUUGGCUGGAGCCACGGCCCACACCGGGUGCAUGCUUAGACUCACCUUCUGCAGUGCUAAUAUCAUCAACCAUUACUUGUGUGACAUACUCCCCCUCCUCCAGCUUUCCUGCACCAGCACCUAUGUCAACGAGGUGGUUGUUCUCAUUGUUGUGGGUAUUAAUAUCAUGGUACCCAGUUGUACCAUCCUCAUUUCUUAUGUUUUCAUUGUCACUAGCAUUCUUCAUAUCAAAUCCACUCAAGGAAGAUCAAAAGCCUUCAGUACUUGUAGCUCUCAUGUCAUUGCUCUGUCUCUGUUUUUUGGGUCAGCGGCAUUCAUGUAUAUUAAAUAUUCUUCUGGAUCUAUGGAGCAGGGAAAAGUUUCUUCUGUUUUCUACACUAAUGUGGUGCCCAUGCUCAAUCCUCUCAUCUACAGUUUGAGGAACAAGGAUGUCAAAGUUGCACUGAGGAAAGCUCUGAUUAAAAUUCAGAGAAGAAAUAUAUUCUAAUUAGAAGCAGUAAUAAUGUAAAACGAUUGAAGAACUUUAAAUUUUUAUUAGUGUGUUCCAUGAAGAGAUUUUGUUGUUUCUACAGAUGGUGUUAUGUGUGAUUUAAUAAACUUGUCUUAUCAUUUCUCUUAUGAAAUCAUCUUGUCUCUUUUUUUGGUUUUGCAUCUCUGGCACUUCUCACAAUUUUACUAAAUAGGUCAUGGCAUCUUUGUAAAAGGAACAUAUGCACUGAUAUUUUUCAUUAUCAUUUUAUAUCCUUCCUCUCUCCUGGGCUGUUCUUAAUUGGACAUAUAUGGUAAAUUUCAUGAAUUAUAAAGAUGUCAAAGUCACGGCUUUCUCACCUAAACUCAGAAGUGCCAAAUAUGAUAGAAGCAUUCUUAUUUUUAUCAACAUUGUUACAGAUAUAGGCAGCUGGAUUUGAUGAAAUGUCUCCAUUACAAAUGGUAGGUAGCUUAAAGCAGAAUGAGCACCCCUUGAUCUUGUCCUUUUGUUCUAUAUUGUCACCAUUUUGCCUUUUAUUAUUCUGACUUUUCUUGUUCCCUUUGAGAAUGGCAAAAUUUGUACCACAUGCCGUUUGCUUCUGAGAACCUCUAUCAGUCCAGUGCAUUUGAUACAGCAGAGAAUAUGUGUGUCUCCACCUUUUAUUGCCAAAGGCAGCAUUUACAGAGGAUGAUUAGAGAAAUAAUACAUGUGGACCUCAGGAUUCCAAUAAGUGGGUCCAUUGUUUACAUUAUAAAACUUUCAUUCAUUGCUAUCUAAAACAGCAUUGAAAAUUUUGAAAAAAGCGUGUAGUUCCUACUGUAAAUGUUAUUUUUUUACUCGUUAUAGGUAAAUACUGCACAUUAAGUUAGCAGAAAUAUUUUACACAAUGGUUAC